CAAAACUCUGGAUCAUCUUUAAAGACCUGUGGCACACAGACCACUGGACAAAGUUCUGCUGCCUCUUUCUCUUGGGAAGUCUGUAAAUAUGAAGCUGUUUCUGGUUCUCAUUAUUCUGCUGUUUGAGGUACUCACAGACGGGGCAAGACUCAAAAAAUGCUUCAAUAAAGUAACAGGCUAUUGCAGGAAGAAAUGCAAGGUAGGAGAAAGAUAUGAAAUAGGAUGUCUAAGUGGGAAAUUAUGUUGUGCUAAUGAUGAAGAAGAGAAAAAACAUGUGUCAUUUAAGAAGCCACAUCAACAUUCUGGUGAGAAGCUGAGUGUGCUGCAGGAUUACAUCAUCUUACCCACCAUCACCAUUUUCACAGUCUAAUCCUAAAUCUAGCCCUUGUCUCGCUGGUCUCCA